CCCUUCCGGUGGAGCCAGCGCUGCGACCGCCUGCAGAAGGUUGACUGCGUGGUAGGGGGCCCAGAGCAAGCCGAAGGCAAGCACGAUGGCGCUCACCAGCCGGCCCACCCGCGCCCCGUGCCGCCCGGAGCCCCAGCGGGCGCCCCGCAGCCGUGCCAGCGUCACGCUGUAGCAGCCGAGCAUCAGCCCGAAAGGAAGCACGAAAGCGGUCAGAGUCUCCAGGCUCAGGUGGGCGGCGGCGUGGACCGGCGACGGGUGGCACAGCUGGCAUACGCGGUCCCUCCACAGGUGGCGGUAGACGGCGGCCGGGACGGCGAGCAACAGGGCGGCCAGCCAGACCGCCAGCAGCAGGCGGCGGGCCAGGGCCGGGCUGCGCAGCCGAGGCGCCAGGAAGGGGCGGGUGACUGCGAGGCAGCGCUGCAGGCUGAGCAGGCCGGUGAGCAGCACGCUGGCGUACAUGCUGAGCGCGCACACGUAGUACACCGCCUUGCAGCCCGCCUGGCCCAGCGGCCAGGCCUGCCGGGUCAGGAAGGCCACAAAGAGCGGCGUGAGCAGCAGCACCGCGCCGUCGGCCAGCGCCAGGUGCAGCACAAGCGUGGCCGCCAGCGGUCGCCCCCGUGCAGGCCGCCAGCCCGCCAAGCUCCACACCACGAAGCCGUUGCCAGGCAGCCCCAGCAGCGCCGCCAGCAGCAGGAAGGCUGUGCCUGUGGCCCGCGAAGUCUUCCAGCUCAGCAGUGUCUCGUUCCCUGGGGGACGGUAGCAGACCGACAUCCUUCUGGGCCUACAGCCUGCCUCUUUUCUGCCUGGGAGUCCUGACUUCCACGAGGACCCAGACCCCACCUCAAACACAACUCCUUCUUGGAACCCAGAUCCCCUGCUCCCAGUCAGUUGACCUGCCCCACUCCUGGCCUCCUUCCCAGAGCUCAGUGGUAAACAGGCAUAAAGUCAUCACCCCAGGCUGUCACUAUCUCUACCACCACUCCUCUAGUCUGGCCCCUCCUUCUUUGUCCAGCCCCAUUCUAGCACAUCUGGGCAAAACUGGAUGGUGGGGUGUAAAGGGACGUGCACAGAUCUACUUACCAAGCUGGGAGCAAGCAGGAUUGGGGGCCUGGAGAAGCUGAAAGGUUAAGCAGCAGUAGGCGAGGUGCCUACUCCUGUCCUGUGCCUAUCACAUUUGCAGAGGGUAAGACAAGAAUGGGGAGGGACAAGAUGAGGCUCAUCCUGGGCCUCUCCUGGGGCCCCUCCCUCACCCUGCUCCUUCCCAUCACCAACGCACCCAGGCGUCCAGGCAUGUGAGAGCCUGCCUUGCCAGGAAACAGCACAAGCUGAAGUGGGGCAGUAAGAUUCCCUGGUGGUGGAAGGAAAUAGGAGGACUCUGCUGAAUCCUGGUCCUGCUUCUGUUCUCAUCCCUCCCCCAGCUCUGGCCCCAAUCCUCCCAGCCCACCUUCUGCAGUGUGUAUGUUGCCUGGUCUCUCUGGCCUGCAGAGGUGACCCAAACAACUCAGUCCCCCACCUGCCUUAUCCUUGCCUGUUUCCAGUCUCCUGGUCCGGCUGAGCCCCUGGCCUCCUACCUCCUCCCACCUCUUGCCUCAGGCCCUGCCCCAGUCACUCCACCCUCAGGGCUCUCACCGGGCUGUCAAUGACAGCUUUUCCAUGUAAGGCAUGGUGCUAGGUUCCAGGAGGAACAGGGGAUGCAUGGAGGCAUAAUGGUUAGGGAGUCAUGACACACAACCAUGAAGAGGCCCCAUUACCAGGCUGCACCAGGAUACAAGACAAGAAAGGAAAGGAUGAGUAGGGACAUACUAAGAAGCAGCCCUCUCCUCUUGGAAAAGUCAAGCAAAACUUGGAAAUGAAGAGAUUUGAGGGGGGCCUGGCAGAUGGAUAGAGCUGGGGGAAGGGAAAAGAAAGGCCUCUGCUCAAGUAACAGCCAGAACUUGAGGUUGCUUGGGGAGGGCACCAGGAGCACUGUCUUAGUUUGGGUUCUUCCAAAGCAGAGCUUGAGCUAAGGGCUUGGGUACAGGUGAUCCUGUAUUCUUGAGCUAAGGGCUUGGGUACAGGUGAUCCUGUAUUUGGGAGGUUAACUCAGGAAGUGAGGGCAUAAGGUAAAACAAGAGAGAGGAAAGCCAUUAAGAGUAUGUUAAGUCCCUUCAGUAGGCCUUGGGAACCUCUGAGAAAAGUAUAGAUUGCCCAAGACAAAAGACUGGCAGGGUGAUCAGUCCAAAGCAUUUAUUAGGAGAAUGUACUUAAUGAGUGGGCUACAGCGUAUCCUCACAACAGACAGUGAGAGAGAGUUGUUCUACCUGGGUAUAUCCAAAACAAGGGGGUCAGGGUAUGGAGUUUACGAGGGUUCAAGGUAUUUGGUUCAGGGCCAGGGCCAGUUUUUUUCAGUGUUUUGGGCAACAACCUGAAUACCUUUUCAAGGCUCUGGCUUGGGCUCAAGCCUGCAGGGGAAAUGCAACUGGCCAGGUCACAGGGCAAUCAAGUUACUCUGUGUUUCUUUGUCAGGACACAGAAAAAAAGUGGGGAAGCUGGGGGACCCUACAAGGAUCCUUGGCAGGAAAGCAGGGAUUGUGUUCAUUUGAGGGUUUCACUGUCAGUGAGAGUCUCAGCUUCCAUGCAACUGUCCAUCACGGCUGCAACUGAAAUCAGAGCUGGGACACAGCGCACCAGAAGCUAAAGUCUUGAUGCCAUCAAAGGACAUCCCUGCCCCAUUCACAUCUCUGUCACGUCCACUAAUCGGCAAAAGGAGAAAAGUGAGAGAAGAUGACCUAAGUGUGACUGCAGCAGGCAGCUCUGGAAAAUGAAGCCAGAGCAGUGAGCCAGCCCCUCCUCCGACCAAGGAGGAAGGAAAGAGCAGCCCCAGCACAGGAGAGAACCACCCAGCCCAGAAGUUCCAGGGAAGGAACUCUCCGGUCCACCAUGGAGUACCUCUCAGCUCUGAACCCCAGUGACUUACUCAGGUCAGUAUCUAAUAUAAGCUCGGAGUUUGGACGGAGGGUCUGGACCUCAGCUCCACCACCCCAGCGACCUUUCCGUGUCUGUGAUCACAAGCGGACCAUCCGGAAAGGCCUGACAGCUGCCACCCGCCAGGAGCUGCUAGCCAAAGCAUUGGAGACCCUACUGCUGAAUGGAGUGCUAACCCUGGUGCUAGAGGAGGAUGGAACUGCAGUGGACAGUGAGGACUUCUUCCAGCUGCUGGAGGAUGACACGUGCCUGAUGGUGUUGCAGUCUGGUCAGAGCUGGAGCCCUACAAGGAGUGGAGUGCUGUCAUAUGGCCUGGGACGGGAGAGGCCCAAGCACAGCAAGGACAUCGCCCGAUUCACCUUUGACGUGUACAAGCAAAACCCUCGAGACCUCUUUGGCAGCCUGAAUGUCAAAGCCACAUUCUACGGGCUCUACUCUAUGAGUUGUGACUUUCAAGGACUUGGCCCAAAGAAAGUACUCAGGGAGCUCCUUCGUUGGACCUCCACACUGCUGCAAGGCCUGGGCCAUAUGUUGCUGGGAAUUUCCUCCACCCUUCGUCAUGCAGUGGAGGGGGCUGAGCAGUGGCAGCAGAAGGGCCGCCUCCAUUCCUACUAAGGGGCUCUGAGCUUCUGCCCCCAGAAUCAUUCCAACCGACCCACUGCAAAGACUAUGACAGCAUCAAAUUUCAGGACCUGCAGACAGUACAGGCUAGAUAACCCACCCAAUUUCCCCACUGUCCUCUGAUCCCCUCGUGACAGAACCUUUCAGCAUAACGCCUCACAUCCCAAGUCUAUACCCUUACCUGAAGAAUGCUGUUCUUUCCUAGCCACCUUUCUGGCCUCCCACUUGCCCUGAAAGGCCAAGAUCAAGAUGUCCCCCAGGCAUCUUGAUCCCAGCCUGACUGCUGCUACAUCUAAUCCCCUACCAAUGCCUCCUGUCCCUAAACUCCCCAGCAUACUGAUGACAGCCCUCUCUGACUUUACCUUGAGAUCUGUCUUCAUACCCUUCCCCUCAAACUAACAAAAACAUUUCCAAUAAAAAUAUCAAAUAUUUACCACUAA